GCAUAUAUUAAAUUUGUCUGACUAGGAAGAGUUAUGUCAGUAAAGCAAUUAGAUACAUGGGUUGUGAUUUGGGGAAAAAAGCUGAAUUAGAAAUCUGUACUUGUAAAUCAUCAACAAGUAUGUAAUCAUUGGUGAUGUUGAUACUGAUGAAAUCAACCUAAAGGUGGAACAAAAAGGACCAAAAAUAGUGACUUAAAAAAACAAUUUAGAAAAAAUCUCAGAACACGAAACAGAAUGUUAAAUUGUCACAGGAGAGAGCUUAUGCCCUUGAAUCAAGGGAAAAUAGAGUUCACAAGGAGCCAGCGGCCGGCAGCAUCACACUUUUAUGACAGACCUGGAAGGGUGUUUUGAAUGCUGUAUCAAAUGCCUGGGGGGCAUUCCCUAUGCCUCUCUGAUUGCCACCAUCCUGCUCUAUGCGGGUGUUGCCCUGUUCUGUGGCUGCGGUCAUGAAGCGCUUUCUGGAACUGUCAACAUUCUGCAAACCUACUUUGAGAUGGCAAGAACUGCUGGAGACACACUGGAUGUUUUUACCAUGAUUGACAUCUUUAAGUAUGUGAUCUACGGCAUCGCAGCUGCGUUCUUUGUGUAUGGCAUUUUGCUGAUGGUGGAAGGUUUCUUCACAACUGGGGCCAUCAAAGAUCUCUAUGGGGAUUUCAAAAUCACCACUUGUGGCAGAUGUGUGAGCGCUUGGUUCAUUAUGCUGACAUAUCUUUUCAUGUUGGCCUGGCUGGGAGUCACGGCUUUCACCUCACUGCCAGUUUACAUGUACUUCAAUCUGUGGACCAUCUGCCGGAACACCACAUUAGUGGAGGGAGCAAAUCUCUGCUUGGACCUUCGUCAGUUUGGAAUUGUGACAAUUGGAGAGGAAAAGAAAAUUUGUACUGUCUCUGAGAAUUUCUUGAGGAUGUGCGAAUCUACUGAGCUGAACAUGACCUUCCACUUGUUUAUUGUGGCACUUGCUGGAGCUGGGGCAGCAGUCAUUGCUAUGGUUCACUACCUUAUGGUUCUGUCUGCCAACUGGGCCUAUGUGAAAGACGCCUGCCGGAUGCAGAAGUAUGAAGACAUCAAGUCGAAGGAAGAGCAAGAGCUUCAUGACAUCCACUCUACUCGCUCCAAAGAGCGGCUCAAUGCAUACACAUAAAUGCAUCUUCCUGUUCUUUCUACCAUUUGAAUGCAUUGGUGUUUAACUAAGGGCCAUCCAACCAUCCAACCUUUAAAAAACAAAACGAAAGUGCUUCUCAUCAAUGAUAUGUAAGGUGACUUAUGAAUCACCUGAGUACAAUUCUUUGUUGUUUAGCACUUAAAUUUCCCAAUUUAUUAAAUUGAUGUAAAUCAGAUCUUUUCUACAAGCUCCUAUCCAGCCUUUUUUUUGAAAUUUCUCAAACUCAUUUACUAGUUCUGUAAAAUCAAAGAUACUAACAUUGUCAAAUGCAAAGAUUUGUUUGAUUUUUAACCACUUCCCAUGUGUUAUACAUAACACCUUUUGCAUUAUUUCUUAUGUUUUGAAAAGAAAAUAGCUUUUUAUACUUUUUAGUUUUGAUUUCGGUAACUAGUUUAACUACAGGUAACCUUCAAAGGGACCAUUGUACAUUAUGAACAAUAGAUAGAGAUUACAUCUUGAUGACUCUUGAAAUAUGGAAAUUUUGUCUGAAGAUCAGUGGCCAUAUUACUGUAGGCCCUGGUUCAUGUUUUCAUCAAUCUAAGGUGCAAUUUCUAAAUUUGUAAGAGUAGGUUUAAAAAAAAAAGUGCUUCUUAUCUUUGUUAACAUUGUACUUUUCCUUGAUGUUCUUAAAAGGUAUUUCCCUCAGAUUACUCAUGUUUAUGUUGUGAGCAUGUAGAAACAGUAAUGCUAAUGCAUGGCUAGUUGCCUUUUUAAGAUUGUGACACCAGGCUUACCUUUUAAAGUUUAGUAUAUAGAGACAAUUUUAAUGGAAAUAACUACUGUAGACUAUUGAAGAAUGAUCUCUUUGUGAUUUAAGAAGUGGCUGGAUUGGAACUUUUAAUAUGCUAAUGUGGAAAAUUAAUUACCUUUAUGAAGGUGGUUUAUUACAAAUAAGCACACUAACCCCUCGGAAGUUGUUUUACCUACUUUAAAAGUUUUAAUGGAUUGCACCUCUGUAAACUAUUCCUAAAAUGUGUAUGAUAUAUUUGAAAAGGCUUCCAUUAAUAUAAUAGCUUUGCUUGCAGCCUUCCAAUCUAUGUUGGUUUACCUGUAGUGUUUUAUAAAGUGUGGUCAGAGGCCCCUAUAGAAUGUAUUGUUUGAAAGUGUAGUGAUAUAUUUGUGUUUUUAUUUCAAGUAAGUCAUUUUAACCGAAUGUUCAUUCAUAUUCAUUUAUAAAAAGUACCUGUAUCAAAGGAAUUUUAACAAAGAGCAAUCAGUAUUAUUGGACCAAAUUUGGUGUUUGUUUUCACCUUGACGCUCUUCUUUUCAUUAUUUCUAAUGCUACAAGAAUGCUGUAAAGUGUCUUCUAAAAUGAUGUAGCCUGACAAGACAUUUUUUUCAGUGUAUAAAACUAGGUAGUAUUGUGCACUGAUUUGACCAUUGUGAAAUCCUUUCUCAGUGUAACUGCAUUUCUAAUAAAAAUUUAUUGAGUGAAACAAUCUUUGUACAAUGACUAGUCAUGCAUCAUCAGUAAUUUUACAAGUUCUUGUAGUAGGUAGGGGGUACUACUAGGGAUAUCUGUGGCAUGAUUAUGCAUUCCGUAGUAUUAUUUAAUUAAUUUGGGGUUCAUUUUGCUUCCUUUUCUUUAUGCUUAGAUUAUCUUACUGGUUCAACAUUUUUCUGAUAUAUGCAGUAUUACAGAUAUUCAGCAAAAGUAUUAAUGGGCUUCUUUAAAUUCUAUAUUAUAGUAUUUCAGUUCCGUGUCUUAACAGUUUGUGAUAAUUUCUAAAACUGUCUUUUCAACUUAUGUAAUGAUGUUGACACUUUUGGCUUUUAUUUCUGGUAUUAGAGUUUGUAUUUUCACAGAGUGCUUUGUAGCAGGCAUUACAAUUAAUCUGUUUUGUACAUAAAUGUGCCAACAGCUUGAUGGUGGCGUUUUUGAAAUGUAGAACAGAGUGCUUGCAAAAUGUAAUAAAUACACUUGUGUACUUUGUGUACUUAUUAUUA